AUUGUCUCCUUGGCCGGACCUGGGCUGCGGAAGGAAGAAGAUGCAAGCCAGCCCCAUCCGUAUCCCAACUGUUAGCAAUGACAUCGACUGGGAUUUCUGCUUCCAUAUGUCACAGCAAACCGAGAUCCCAGCUCACCAGCAAACAGAUGAGUUGUAUCCCACUGGUGGGUGUGGAGAGAGUGAAGAGGAAACUAAAGCUAAAGAGAAGGAGAAGGCCAUAGACUGUAUGUCUCAUCCCAAAGAGAAAUUAGCCCAAUCCCAGAAGAAAGUAGCUCAGCUGAUUAAGGAAAAAAUGAAUACUCAAGCAAACAAGGAGCUGAUUCGAUGUGUCAUCCUUUCUCGGAUUAUUUUUGGGGACCAUCACUGGAAAUGUGCACGAGCUCUGGCCAACCUAGCUUAUGGCUACUUGACACUGAGAGGCCUCCCAGUUCAGGCCAAGAAACAUGCUACAUCAGCCAAGAAUACACUGUUGACCUGGAAGGCAAAUACGACCUCAAAUAAGGAGAAAGAGGAAAUCCUGGAAGCUCUGGUCAAGCUGUACUACACUCUGGGCGUGGCCUGGCUCCUGCAGAACCGUGGCAGAGAAGCCUAUUUCAACCUGCAGAAGGCAGAGAGAAACAUGAAGGAGCUGAAAGAAUUAUAUAAAGGAGGUGUUUGUGAAUUACAAGUCUCUGAGAACGACCUAACACUUGCUUUGGGCAGAGCCUCCUUGGCCAUCCACAGACUGAACCUAGCUCUGGCAUACUUUGAAAAGGCAAUUGGCGAUGUUAUUGCUGCCAAGGGUGAUAGGACGUCAGAUCUGAUCAGCCUGUACGAGGAAGCUGCUCAGAUAGAGCAGCUGAGGAGGAACCACAACCAGGCCAUCCAGUACUUGCAGCAGGCUCAUUCUGUCUGUGUUUCUUUGUUCACUGAAGUCAGCCCCAAAACUGCAGAAAUGAGUGCGUUACUGGCCAAAGCUUAUGCCAUGUCUGGAGAGGCCCAGCACAGGGAUGCUGUUGAGAUAUAUUUCAUAAGAAGUAUCAAUGCAUAUCGAGCAACAUUGGGCUCAGAGGAUUUUGAAACACUGAGCACCACUGAAGAAUUUUGCAAAUGGCUUGUCCAAAAUGGAGAAAAACAGUGUCUGAUGAUUCAAAUCUUUGUAUAUGGAGGUGAACACAGUAGAAGUAGGGAGACAAAGAGCCUCCUUACCCUGUGGCAGAGGACAAGUAGCAGUUCAUCCAGAUGGAGAAGAGAAGCCAUUCCUGGAAGAAGGAACUCUACAUACAAAGGCACAGAAGCAUGACAGAGGGCAGUGUAUGGAGGAAUGGUAAGUACUUUACAGCUGUUGUACAGGGCAGCAUGUCCUGAAAGGGGCUGCAAGAAAUGCUGAUUCCAAGGGAUGUGUGCCAGUUCUCUGGGGGAGGAAGAAAGGCUCUGUAGCAGAAAGACAAAAAUCAUUUAAGGAAAAAAAAAAACAAAAAAAACAGGUUUAAACAAAGUGACACAGGUUACUUUUCUGAAGGGCUUCUCAGGACUUUUAAUAUACAAAACCUUCGGCUGGGUGCUGUAGCUCAUGCUGUAAUCCUAGCACUUUCAGAGGCUGAGGCAGGUGGAUUGUCUGAGCUCAGGAGUUCGAGACCAGCCUGGGAAACACAGUGAAACCCAGUCUCUACUAAAAUACAAAAAAUUAGCCGGGCGUGGUAGCAUGCGCCUGUAGUCCCAGUUACUCGGGAGGCUGAGGCAGGAGAAUUGCUUGACCUGGGAGGUGGAGGUUGCAGUGAGCCGAGAUUGUGCCACUGCACUACAGCCUGGGCAACAGAGCAAGACUGUCUCCUAAAGAAAAAUAAAAAAAAAAUUAAACAUUAAAAAAAAUACAUAUAUAUACAAAACCUUCCUUAUUGGCAUGUUGGGAACAAAUCAGGUUUUUAACAUUUUUAUUUUUAUAUUUUAAAUUUGUAGUGACGAGGUCUCACUAUGUUGCCCAGGCUGGCCUCCAACUCCUUGGCUCAAGUGAUCCUCCCGCCUCAGCCUCUCAAAGUCCUGGGAUUACAGGCAUGAACACACCAUACCUGGCUGCAAAUCAGUUUUUUAGAAACCAUUGUAUUUUACAUACCUAAAGUCUUUUUGAAAUGAUCAGUGAUUUAAAUUUUGGCAAAUAAAACCUUGCCCUGUCUUUAGAAUCAAAGUAGAGAAACUAAGGUUUGGUUUUGUUGAAAGCAAAGGGUGUAGUGUAUACUUGCCCUGAGGGUAUACAUGAAUACUUUUGCAGUUUGGUAAGGAAUUUUGGCCCCACUUUAGGACAUAAAGUCUUUAUGAACUAUGAUUAUCUCAUCAACUAUUUAAUCUGAUCAUAGAAAUAUGACUUCAGUGCAUCCCUAUGAAUUAAUCUUUUUGAUUCAUGGUGGUUAAGAGCUGUAGUUCUGGAGACAGGCAAGCCUGAGUUCAAACCCCAGGACUACCACUUUCUAGCUAUGGGCAAUCCUGGUUUCUUCAUCUAUAAAAUGGGGAUGAAGUAUAGUACCUAUCUCAGUGUUGUUGUGAGAAUAAAUGAGAUAAUGCAUUAUAUGUAAAGUGCUUAGCAGAGUGCCUGGCCCCAUAGUAAUCAUGUACUAAGUAACAGCUAUUUUUAGUUUUACUGAAAGCUGGUCUUUGACUUUAUUACCUUCUACUGGCACCACUGUUGCACGAAGCAAACGGAGAUAGGGGCUGAAUAUUUUGAAAAGCUACUACCAAGCUGAUGUGGAAAAUAUUUUGCUGGUUAACAUCUCGAAAAAGAUAUAGACUUAUCAGGUUCUGGAAACACUGUUAGUCUCAUAGACAAGCAGUCUGACACAGUCACCUAAACUCAAAGAUAAUAUAUACACUAUGGAAAUCAGUUGUCCUUUCAGGUUUCAGACAAGGGGAAUCCUGCCACCUUGUGGUGCGACAGAAGUAGGCCCGAGGCUGAUUCCCACUUACUAUCCCUAGCAGAGAUGCAGCCCUCUUACAGUUCUUUGCCCACCUCUGAAUUUAUGAGACCCCUGGGCAACUAACUUAAUCUGUGCCUAUUUCUUCAGCUAAUUUGGAAUCUCAUUAUCUCCUGGUUUACUGCAAAGGAAGUUAAAGUGCCAGAUAGCUUUCUAUAUUUUAUACAGUCCAGUAAUAGAGAAUGAGCCUGUCUUUAGUGCAACUUGCAUAGAAACCCCAAGUUCAUAAAAUUUUGUAUUUCAUAUUCUACAGAACAAAUAUUCUUUUCAAGUAAAAAAAGGGCUAUGAAAACCACUUUUUUCAGGCUUGAGGUAGAAAUAGGAGGUGACUAAAGAACACUUAAUAGUAACUGUGUUUCUGGAGCAGUCUUUUGGAUCAUAAUACAUCAAAUUCCUGCUCAGCUCCUUCAGUAAUGGGAAAUCAGAGGACAGACAUCUCAACGGCUAGAAACAAGCAAGAGAGAUCUUUCACAGGGCCUCGGGCUGUAAGUCUCCGAGCUCGUGAGAAGAAACCACUUGAAAAUCAUCAACUAUAUAAAAGGCCCUAAAUUAGAUAAGUUUUCCACCUGGGAUUUAAACAAUCCAGGUGGCUCAAAUAUCCCUGGUUUGCCAUCUGAAUCAAGGGAAGAGCUCCCUGCUGUUUAGGAAGAAAACCCGAGACUCUAGUAAGAUUUUAGAGGCCUAUUAGAAGAGCCAGCAUUUUGAGAGUAUAGUCAUGUGGUGGAAUAAUGGUGACACAGUCGCCUCAGGCUAAGUUCAGCCUUUGGCUCAGGUAAGGCAAUGAGAUCUGCUGCUGGGGGAGGCAGGGCCAGUUAUGGAGGAAGAGAAGGCAAGAACCAAGAAAAAUGCUCAAAUGGUUUUCUCCUUUCCUCUAGGUCUUCUGUUAUCAAAUUGAAAACCUCUAUACAGGAUAGCCAACAAUAAAGACAACCUUGUUGAUGAUAAAAAUUCUCGACCACAAAAUGUUUCUCAACACUGAUAGCAGUGGCAGAUCUAAAACAACGGUUUUUUAUUAAGGACUCUGGGAAAAAAAGGUCCACUUAGCAGCAGCAUUCCAGGUGAAAUACCCAAGAGCCAUUAGAAACUAGGAUCCUGGCUGGGCGCGGUGGCUCAUGCCUAUAAUCCCAGCACUUUGGGAGGCCGAGGCAGGCCAAUCAUGAAGUCAGGAGAUUGAGACCAUCCUGGUCAACACGGUGAAACCCCAUCUCUACUAAAAAUACAAAAAAAAUUAGCUGGGCGUGGUGACACAUGCCUGUAAACCUAGCUACUCGGGAGGCUGAGGCAGAAGAAUCACUUGAACCGGGGUCGGAGGUUGCAGUGAACUGGGAUCAUGCCACUGCACUCCAGCCUGGCGACAGAUAGAGACUGCGUCUCAAAAAAAACAAACAAAAAACAAACAAACAAACCCAACUAGGAUCCUGAUCUAUGACUUGGGGGAAAGAAAUCUUUUAGUCACAUGCUUUAAGUUAGUUUUUUGUGUCACUGGAACUCCAUUACCUUCCAUUUCCCUUUUUCUAACUCUAUUCCUUUCAGUUCUGACUUUUUAAAAAAUUCUGCGAUACCUAAGGAGUUUAUUGGUGAACACUUUCAUGUACUACAGUUGACCACUGAACAAUGCAGGGGCUAGGGCUGCCAAUGCCUUGUGCAGUCAAAAAUCUUUGUAUAACUUUGGAUUCCCCCAAAACUUAACUGCUAAUAGCCUACUGUUAACUGGGAGCCUUACUGAUAAGCUUAACAGUUGAUUAACACAUAUUUUGUAUGUUAUAUGUAUAGUAUAUAAUAUAUUCUUACAAUAAGUAAACUAGAGAAAGGCAAAGGUUAUUAAGAAAAUGAUAAGGGGCCAAGUGUGGUGGCUCAUUGCCUGUAAUCCUAGCACUCUGGGAGGCAGAGGAAGGCAGACUGCUUGAGCCCAGGAGGUCGAGGCUGCAGUGAGCUGAGAUUGUGCCACUGCACUCCAGCCUGGAUGAGAAAGUGAGACCCUGUUCAAAAAAAAAAAAGAAAGAAAAUAAGGAAAUACAUUUACAUUACUGUAUUUAUUGAUUCCGUUAAGUUUACAUUGUCUGUUUACAGAAAGAAUCCUGGGACUGAAAUGAGGGGCAUCCACAGCCACAGACCUCAAUCUUUGAUACAUAUCAAGCAAUUCAGCUUUUUCUUGUAAUGUCAUGACUUCUACUUCUUGAGAACACUUCCAGCAUCACUAGUGGCACUUCAUAUGGGUCCCAUGGUAUUAUAUGAGGUUUAUGGUGCACUAAACAUGAUGAAAAAUACUUAAGAAUCUCGAGAGAGUACUUUUUUCUGCCACAUGAAAUUUACUGGAGAGUUGAACUGCUCAUGCAGAGAUGAUUAGCAUCACAUAGCGUUUUGAGUGGAUAUUCACAACAUCUGCGCGCACUGCCGCAGCAGUAGGAGGCAGCUACAAAAUGAUUGCAGUACAGUACGUACUCCAGUUGGUUUUAUGUGGCUAUGAUUUAACCUUGCAUCUUUACAUUUGUUUACAUUUCUCUGGACUGUGAAUGGCACCAUGUACUGUAUAUGUGUGUAAAUUUUGAGAAAAUUUAGCUUUUUAUAAUAGAUUUGUGCAUAUUUUGUAGUAGCAAAUGAUAAAAUAGACUAGUAUAUACAUAUAUUUUAUGCAUUCAUACCUUUUAAAAUGUUUAAAAAUAUUUCUAGGCAACGCAGUUUGUGUUUUUUCAAAUUGUCAAAAAACUCCAAAAAAAAAAACUUCCAAUGUAUUUAUUGAAAAAAAUCUGUGUAUAAGUGGAUUUACACAGUUCAAACCCAUGUUGUUCAAGGGUCAACUGUAUUUGGAGGUGUUUUUAGUCAUAGCCUGUUUGAGGUCACCAAAACUGCCUUGGGAGGAAUAGUUUGAACCUUCUGAAACACUUACCCUGAUCUGAUUUACUGAACUCGUCAUAACAUGUUCAAAGUCAGAAAGGACCAUUUUAUUUUAUAAAGAAACUGGGGACGGCCGGGCAUGGUGGCUCAAGCCUGUAAUCCCAGCACUUUGGGAGGCCGAGGCAGGCGGAUCAUCUGAGGUCAGGAGUUUGAGACCAGCCUGACCAACAUGGAGAAACCCUGUCUCUACUAAAAAUACAGAAUUAGCUGGGUGUGGUGGCGCAUGCCUGUAAUCCCAGCUACUCGGGAGGCUGGGGCAGGAGAAUUGCUUGAACCUGGGAGGUGGAGGUUGCGGUGAGCUGAGAUCAUGCAAUUGCACUCCAGCUUGGGCAACAAGAGCAAAACUCCAUCUCAAAAACAAAAACAAAACAACAACAAAAGAAACUAGGGACAAGAGAGUGAUUUGUUCAAGGUCAGCUUGGUAAUUAUAAAGCAGACUUCCUGGAUCACAGAUGAUUACUCUUUCCAUCCCACUCUGCUGCCUCCACCAAACUGGAUUAAAAAGGCUUGUUUUAGGAACAGAAUACUCACUGUGGUUGUUUAUGAAGAAAAUCCUUAGACUCUGAGCAAGUGUAUAUCUAGCGAAAGAAUUUGCAAUCUUGAAUAAUAUUCCUUACUUUCUUGUGAAUUUAGCGACAGAGAAAUCUCAUUUGGGUUUGCACUAUAAAUAACUUUAAUUUUUCUCUCUUCAUCUUUUCCCAGUUGUCUAACUUGAUUUAAUACAGCUCAAAUGGCCGGGCGCGGUGGCUUAAGCCUGUAAUCCCAGCACUUUGGGAGGCUGAGGCAGGGGGAUCACCUGAGGUCACGAGUUCCAAGACCAGCCUGGCCAACACGGCUCUCUACCAAAAAUACAAAAAUUAGCUGGGCAUGGUGGUGGGUGCCUGUAAUCCCAGGUGCUUGGGAGGCUGAGACAGGAGAAUCACUUGAACCUGGGAGGUGGAGGUUGCAGUGAGCCAAGAUUGUGCCAUUGCAGUCCAGACUGGGUGACAAGAGCAAAACUCCCUCUAAAAAAUAAAUUAAUAAUAAUACAGCUCAAAGACCCUGUGUCUUUGGGGAUCCAAGUGUAUCACUAUCAACAUCUAUAUCAACGCACUCAGUGCUUACAGAACCACAUUUUGGUUCUUCAUUCAGGAAAUUAUUUCAGUCAUUUGUUCAGCCUGUAAAAUCUAAGAAUCAACCAGUACCCAAGGUAUAGUGAGUUGUGUUCUGCUGUGGCAGAAGCACACAUAUACUAACUAAGCCAAAGCCUUGUCCACUGACUGGUAGGCCUUCUCCUGGCAGUUGCCGACUAACUCCCAGGAUGCUUUAGGGUUGGCACUCAGGAUCAAGGUCCCACAUUGCAGACCUGGCUGAAAGCAGCUAUAUAUUCCAUUGCCCUUCUCUGUGGUGCUUAUUAACUGGUCACUUGGCCUAUCAUUGUUCAUUUUAGCCCUUUCUGGAGAUGGGGCUGCUGUUCUUCCCCAGAAUAUUCUGAAUUGAUUACAGUAGCAUCAGAAGAGUUGCUUCCAUUUUCACAUACGUAGUUGAAAAUAGCUCUUCAACAAUGACUGACAUUAAAAAAAAAAAAAUACCAGAAAGAAAUGGCCAUUCAGACUCCAUUUUGGGUGGCACCAAAAUUUAUAAAAUGUUACUAUUUUGCAAUCCUAAGAUCUCCAAACUGACAAACCUAUAUCAAUAAACAGUAGCAUAACACUGUGAAAUAAAAUUUUAUGGUGUACCUGUU